AUAUUUUUCCCAGACGCGGAGGUUGGGGUCAUGGCGCCCCGAAGCCUCCUCCUGCUGCUCUCAGGGGCCCUGGCCCUGACCGAUACUUGGGCGGGCUCCCACUCCUUGAGGUAUUUCAGCACCGCUGUGUCGCGGCCCGGCCGCGGGGAGCCCCGCUACAUCGCCGUGGAGUACGUAGACGACACGCAAUUCCUGCGGUUCGACAGCGACGCCGCGAUUCCGAGGAUGGAGCCGCGGGAGCCGUGGGUGGAGCAAGAGGGGCCGCAGUAUUGGGAGUGGACCACAGGGUACGCCAAGGCCAACGCACAGACUGACCGAGUGGCCCUGAGGAACCUGCUCCGCCGCUACAACCAGAGCGAGGCUGGGUCUCACACCCUCCAGGGAAUGAAUGGCUGCGACAUGGGGCCCGACGGACGCCUCCUCCGCGGGUAUCACCAGCACGCGUACGACGGCAAGGAUUACAUCUCCCUGAACGAGGACCUGCGCUCCUGGACCGCGGCGGACACCGUGGCUCAGAUCACCCAGCGCUUCUAUGAGGCAGAGGAAUAUGCAGAGGAGUUCAGGACCUACCUGGAGGGCGAGUGCCUGGAGUUGCUCCGCAGAUACUUGGAGAAUGGGAAGGAGACGCUACAGCGCGCAGAUCCUCCAAAGGCACACGUUGCCCACCACCCCAUCUCUGACCAUGAGGCCACCCUGAGGUGCUGGGCCCUGGGCUUCUACCCUGCGGAGAUCACGCUGACCUGGCAGCGGGAUGGGGAGGAACAGACCCAGGACACAGAGCUUGUGGAGACCAGGCCUGCAGGGGAUGGAACCUUCCAGAAGUGGGCCGCUGUGGUGGUGCCUUCUGGAGAGGAACAGAGAUACACAUGCCAUGUGCAGCACGAGGGGCUGCCCCAGCCCCUCAUCCUGAGAUGGGAGCAGUCUCCCCAGCCCACCAUCCCCAUCGUGGGCAUCGUUGCUGGCCUUGUUGUCCUUGGAGCUGUGGUCACUGGAGCUGUGGUCGCUGCUGUGAUGUGGAGGAAGAAGAGCUCAGGUAGGAA